AUGCCACCUCCCUUGCCCUCAUCUCUCACUGCCAUGCAAGAAAGCGUUAAUGGCAAAUAGGGCACGUAGCCACACUCCGUCGUUCCUGCUUCCAAGCAAACCUUGUGCCAGGUUCCUCAUUUCGCGAGGCUCCACUCUCUUGGGCUUCAGGCUGCCGCUGGGCCUCCAGCACCAAAGGGCAAUAGGGGUCUGAGAGUCCGGGCCUCAGGCAUCUUCAGGCCGCAGACUGGCAUAGUGAGUAUGGUAUACACACAAUCGGAGAUUCUACAGAAGGAAGUGUACCUCUUUGAACGCAUUGAUUCUCAAAAUCGAGAGAUCAUGAAACACCUGAAGGCAAUUUGUUUUCUUCGACCUACAAAGGAGAAUGUGGAUUAUAUUAUUCAGGAGCUCCGAAGACCCAAAUACACUAUAUAUUUCAUUUAUUUCAGUAAUGUGAUCAGCAAGAGUGACGUGAAGUCAUUGGCUGAAGCUGAUGAACAGGAAGUUGUGGCUGAGGUUCAGGAAUUUUAUGGUGAUUACAUUGCUGUGAACCCACAUUUGUUUUCCCUCAAUAUUUUGGGUUGCUGCCAGGGUCGAAAUUGGGAUCCAGCCCAGCUAUCUAGAACAACUCAAGGGCUUACAGCUCUCCUUUUAUCUCUGAAGAAGUGUCCCAUGAUUCGUUAUCAGCUCUCAUCAGAGGCAGCAAAGAGACUUGCAGAGUGCGUUAAGCAAGUGAUAACUAAAGAAUAUGAACUGUUUGAAUUCCGUCGGACAGAGGUUCCUCCAUUGCUCCUUAUUUUAGAUCGCUGUGAUGAUGCCAUCACCCCAUUGCUAAACCAGUGGACAUAUCAGGCCAUGGUCCACGAACUACUAGGCAUAAACAACAAUCGGAUUGAUCUUUCCAGAGUGCCGGGAAUCAGUAAAGACUUAAGAGAAGUGGUCCUAUCUGCUGAAAAUGAUGAAUUCUAUGCUAAUAAUAUGUACCUGAACUUUGCUGAGAUUGGUAGCAAUAUAAAGAAUCUCAUGGAAGAUUUUCAGAAGAAGAAACCAAAAGAACAGCAAAAACUAGAAUCAAUAGCAGACAUGAAGGCGUUUGUUGAGAAUUAUCCACAGUUCAAGAAAAUGUCUGGGACUGUUUCAAAGCAUGUGACAGUGGUUGGAGAACUGUCUCGAUUGGUCAGUGAACGGAAUCUGCUGGAGGUUUCAGAGGUUGAGCAAGAACUGGCCUGUCAAAAUGACCAUUCUAGUGCUCUCCAGAAUAUAAAAAGGCUUCUGCAGAACCCCAAAGUGACAGAGUUUGAUGCUGCCCGCCUGGUGAUGCUUUAUGCUUUACAUUAUGAGCGACACAGCAGCAAUAGCCUGCCAGGACUAAUGAUGGACCUCAGGAAUAAAGGUGUUUCUGAGAAGUAUCGAAAGCUCGUGUCUGCAGUUGUUGAAUAUGGUGGUAAACGAGUCAGAGGAAGUGACCUCUUCAGCCCCAAAGAUGCUGUGGCUAUCACCAAACAAUUCCUCAAAGGACUGAAGGGAGUAGAAAAUGUAUAUACACAGCAUCAACCUUUCCUACAUGAAACCCUGGAUCAUCUCAUCAAAGGAAGGCUUAAGGAAAACCUAUAUCCUUAUUUAGGCCCCAGCACACUCAGAGACAGACCUCAGGAUAUCAUUGUGUUUGUAAUUGGAGGAGCCACCUAUGAAGAGGCUCUAACAGUUUAUAACCUGAACCGCACCACUCCUGGAGUGAGGAUUGUCCUGGGAGGCACCACAGUGCACAACACGAAAAGUUUCCUAGAGGAAGUUCUGGCUUCUGGACUGCACAGCCGAAGCAAGGAGAGCUCUCAAGUCACAUCAAGGUCAGCGAGCAGAAGAUGAAACGGUGGUUGGGGGAAGGGCACAGCUUCCUCUCUUGUCCCCACUACAGGUUUUCCCUACUAAACAAAGGUGUUGGAGAGCAGCUUUGGGUUCUGUGCUGGUUGUUAGAACUCAUCUCCAGGUAGCCCACGGAUACGUGGUUGGCACAGACACAAGACUCCCAGAGUUGUCCUAACAAUAAGUCUGAGCCCAUCUCAACCCACUUUUCUCCGGUAGUCUUUAUGUAUCUGUUAGCACAAUCACUUCAGUUACUGAUGAAUUUUGUUGGGAUCUGACUUGGGGAAAGGGUUAUCAGAGCCUAGAGGGGCUUAAAAAGUAAUCAUUUGAUGUACAUACCACACUCCUUGGCUUCCUUUCUCUUCCCUUAACCCUUUCUGCUUUUCAUUAACCACAUUCCUGCACAACUCAUUUCUGAAAACCUACCAUGUUUCUUUACAGAGCCAUCCAAAAAUUUUUUGUCCCUACAUAGCAAUUUUCUGUGGCACUGAGAAACCAUGUAUGACCACAAUAAAAAUCCAUUUUGUGAAAGGAUA